UAUUGCGGUGCGAGCCAAAGGUCACUUCAAAGGCUUAUGGCUGCGCGCUUUAGUCUUUAGAAGCGCCGGGAACGCUUUGUGUGAGGCUUUCCCGGGUGUAGUUUAGUGCUCGCAAACUACUGAGUCGACAAAUUGCACAGGGCAGAUGCAAGAGGGGGACUCUGUCUCUCUCCUUUCACCUGACGGGGGGUGGUCACCCGCUGAGCGGUGACAGUGGUGGGGGAGCUUGGUCUGUGGCUUUGGGUGGGGGUGGAAAGGAUGUUUGUUUCUUAGGCGAUUUGCAGUCUGAUCCUGACCCAGAAGUGGGCAGCCCAGGGCCAAGAGUGUGGUGGAUACUUACCGGAAUGAAUAAACUCAGGGAAAGCAUCUGAUAUAUUUAAUGUAUAAAUCAGGAACUAGCGCCCAGGUCCUCUUCACUGAGGCUCUGUAGAGCAGCCCCUGACCAAGAUCCACCCAAGCCUAUUUACCUUCCUUUCCUGGUGCCCUUUUCUGCAGCCUCCCCUGCCAAACCCCCACCUUAAUUCUGCACGGUCUCUCUCUUCUGCCCCUAGGAGAGUGUUUGGCUUCCGGGAUUGGGACCUGGAGGAGCAUUUAGAAUUUGGUAGGGGCAGGAGGAGAGCAGAUUGGCUUCCCUGCACCUCUGACCCACCUGGCUAGAGGGUCUGGCGCUUCCCUCACGUCCGGGCUCUCCCCUCCCCCAUCCAGCCAUGGAUUUUGGCGUUAAAGGGGCCCUCGCUCCCCAGGAGCCAACUGAGUCUGUGUUUUGCCGGGGAGAAGGCGUCUGGAUGGUCACGGGUACCAUAUACAAUAGUCACAUUGACUAUGACGUCCUUCAAGUGGGAAAAGCCCUUCAACAUGUAAGUGUUUGUAAGCAAGAACCGGCUGCUACUGAGAGUUUUCCAUUUUGUUCCAGAUUCGCCUCCACAGAUAUCAAAAGAAACCUGAAGAGCCUACAAAAAAAAAAGAGAUAAAGACAAAAUUCAAGAAAACACACACAUACAUAAUUGUGGUGAGUGGGCAUCAUUUAAAUAAUAAUUUCCAGUACAUUUCCCUCUGCAACUCAAGGUGGCCAUCUCAAAAUUCAUACAUCAAGACAUAGAACAAAGGGCAGCUUUGAAGUGGGUCACUUCAGUAUGAAGUACCACCCGUUACAUGAAAACCGAUCAUUGGCCUUCAAAUUUAUGGCGCUUUAAUGGGGCAAGCCCAGUGCCUUAAAUACAGGGUGCAUUACAGUAUUGAGUUAUCUGGGCUAAAUAAGAGUGAUUUAGAAGGCGCGUCCAGGUCUUCUUAUAGAGCAAAAGAGGCUCAAGCUUAGAGAUCGGGAGAACUUGGGCGGAACGUAAAGAAGUCUCCUUUCGAGCAAACCCAAAAACCAGUGGUUUCGAAUCCCGAAGUAGCAAAGCCAACAGGAAAGGGAGAAUCGUUGCUCGGUUCCAGUGAAUUCGUGGGGAUGCUCAGCAAAAGUCUUGGCCGCCAGAAAGAGAUCCGUGGGCUUCUGACCCUGGUUUAGGCAAAACAGGGGGAGGCGCCGAGACCAGCUCGAGCACUAGCGGAUUUUGAGAGAAACUGACCGCAACCUCCAUCGCCUUCCCCCUCUCUUUCAACUUGGAUGGGCUGACUCUACCCGUCGGUGAUUUACGACGAUUGCAGCGCUAGUCACAGCCUGGCGCCUGGUGUCCCCUCCCUUCCCAAGCCCCCUCAGCUUUUCCACUGCCACCGGCGUACAAGCAAGUGCCGAGCCGGCCUCCGCAAGUCGGACUAGCCUCCCGGCGUCCGAGGCCACCACGGGCAGCAGAUUUUUGGUCCCCAGCGAGGCUGCGCGCGUUCGUCCCGCCUCCGACCGCCGAGCAGAGCUGCUAGCAGAAGCAGGCGCCGGUCACUUUAUAUAAUCCUGCUGCUCGCAGGGUGCAAGAGCGGGAAAAGUGCGGAGUAGGGAAUUCUUUUGCUGCGCUGCCUCCUACGCGGAGCCUGCUUUCCACUGCUGAAAAGUGCCGGGCCUUGGGAAGUGUUUUUCUUUUCAUUCCUUACCGAAGCGUUUACUGCCGCCGUGGUCGCAGUCAUAAAUUUUGCUACAAACCACAAUGACAGGUGCAUUGAUAUGCACCGUGAGAGCUCCAGCUGCUUAAUAACCCCGUCCCCUGGUCGCUGUGAGCGCCUUUUAUUUAUUUGGUAUCAUAUUAGGUAUUGAUCUCUAGUAGCAUUAAGUGCGGUGAGCAAGUAUCAGGGUUCGGCUGCUUUGGAGGCGCAGCGGUUGCGGCGGGCCGGCGGGCCCGGGGAAGCGGGCGGUGGCCGCUCAGAGAAUACCUUCCUUCCGGCAGGAGACCGUUUGGCCCUGUAUUCCGGGCCUGCGGUUGGGCCUCCAAGCUGAGUUGGGCAACUUCCCAGCACCGCAAGAAAGGGCGAGCCAGACCUAUUUGGCACCCCUUUCCCAGGAGGAGCAGGGGAUGGCGCCGGCGGAGUUUGGGGAGGCUGCCCUGGCCAGUUCCCCGGGCUAGAGGGUGGAGGAGAGGAGGAGGGAGAGGAAAGGGCAGCUGAGGACUUGGAAGAAAUGAGAAGCCGUGCUCGACCACCCCUCCCCCAACACUGGCUCAUCUUCACCCCAAGACAUUUGGGUCUUGGAGCCCAAAUGAGCAAAGGUCACCUGGAGCCUGGGGGCCGGCCCAGCUCUCUCAGGAUUCAGCAGACAUUGGAGGUGGCAGUGAAGGAUACAGUGGUAGUCAAUGUUAUUUGAGCAGGGUCAGCAGGCCCUGGAGCUUCCUGAGUGCACAAUGCAGAAGGCUGCUUACUAUGAAAACCCAGGACUGUUUGGAGGCUAUGGCUACAGCAAAACUACGGACACUUACGGCUACAGCACCCCCCACCAGCCCUACCCACCCCCUGCUGCUGCCAGCUCCCUGGACACUGACUAUCCAGGUUCUGCCUGCUCCAUCCAGAGCUCUGCCCCUCUGAGAGCCCCAGCCCACAAAGGAGCUGAACUCAAUGGCAGCUGCAUGCGGCCGGGCACUGGGAACAGCCAGGGUGGGGGUGGUGGCAGCCAGCCUCCUGGUCUGAACUCAGAGCAGCAGCCACCACAACCCCCUCCUCCACCACCGACCCUGCCCCCAUCUUCACCCACCAAUCCUGGAGGUGGAGUGCCUGCCAAGAAGCCCAAAGGUGGGCCCAAUGCUUCUAGCUCCUCAGCCACCAUCAGCAAGCAGAUCUUCCCCUGGAUGAAAGAGUCUCGACAGAACUCCAAGCAGAAGAACAGCUGUGCCACUGCAGGAGAGAGCUGCGAGGACAAGAGCCCGCCAGGCCCAGCAUCCAAGCGGGUACGCACGGCAUACACGAGCGCGCAGCUGGUGGAAUUGGAAAAGGAAUUCCACUUCAACCGCUACUUGUGCCGGCCGCGCCGCGUGGAGAUGGCCAACCUGCUGAAUCUCACGGAACGCCAGAUCAAGAUCUGGUUCCAGAACCGGCGCAUGAAGUACAAGAAGGACCAGAAGGCCAAGGGCAUCCUGCACUCGCCGGCUAGCCAGUCCCCUGAGCGCAGCCCACCGCUCGGCGGCGCCGCUGGCCACGUGGCCUACUCCGGCCAGCUGCCGCCAGUGCCCGGCCUGGCCUACGACGCGCCCUCGCCGCCUGCUUUCGCCAAAUCACAGCCCAAUAUGUACGGCCUGGCCGCCUACACGGCGCCACUCAGCAGCUGCCUGCCACAACAGAAGCGCUACGCAGCGCCGGAGUUCGAGCCCCAUCCCAUGGCGAGCAACGGCGGCGGCUUCGCCAGCGCCAACUUGCAGGGCAGCCCGGUGUACGUGGGCGGCAACUUCGUCGAGUCCAUGGCGCCCGCGUCCGGGCCUGUCUUCAACCUGGGCCACCUCUCGCACCCGUCGUCGGCCAGCGUGGACUACAGUUGCGCCGCGCAGAUUCCAGGCAACCACCACCAUGGACCUUGCGACCCUCAUCCCACCUACACAGAUCUCUCGGCCCACCACUCGUCUCAGGGACGACUGCCGGAGGCUCCCAAACUGACGCAUCUGUAGCGGCCGCCGCCAGCCCGAACUCGCGGCAAAAUUACCUCUCUUGCUGUAGUGGUGGGGUAGAGGGUGGGGCCCGCGGGGCAGUUCGGGAACCCCCUUCCCCGCUCUUGCCCUGCCGCCGCCUCCCGGGUCUCAGGCCUCCAGCGGCGGAGGCGCAGGCGACCGGGCCUCCCCUCCAUGGGCGUCCUUUGGGUGACUCGCCAUAAAUCAGCCGCAAGGAUCCUUCCCUGUAAAUUUGACAGUGCCACAUACUGCGGACCAAGGGACUCCAAUCUGGUAAUGGUGUCCCAAAGGUAAGUCUGAGACCCAUCAGCGGCGCGCCCUGCAGAGGGACCAGAGCUUGGAGAGUCUUGGGCCUGGCCCGCGUCUAGCUUAGUUUCAGAGACCUUAAUUUAUAUUCUCCUUCCUGUGCCGUAAGGAUUGCAUCGGACUAAACUAUCUGUAUUUAUUAUUUGAAGCGAGUCAUUUCGUUCCCUGAUUAUUUAUCCUUGUCUGAAUGUAUUUAUGUGUAUAUUUGUAGAUUUAUCCAGCCGAGCUUAGGAAUUCGCUUCCAGGCCGUGGGGGCCACAUUUCACCUCCUUAGUCCCCCUGGUCUGAACUAGUUGAGAGAGUAGUUUUGAACAGUCGUAACCGUGGCUGGUGUUUGUAGUUGACAUAAAGGAUUAAGACCGCAAAUUGUCCUUCAUGGGUAGAGUCAGGAAGCCCGGUGGCGUGGCACAACACACUUUGGUCAUUUCUCAAAAACCACAGUCCUCACCACAGUUUAUUGAUUUCAAAUUGUCUGGUACUAUUGGAACAAAUAUUUAGAAUAAAAAAAUUUCCCAGUC